CUCAUUUUUCUCUUGCCAUCGCCAUGAAAGAAGUGCCUUUCACCUCCCACCAUGAUUCUGAGGCCUCCCCAGCCAUGUGGAACUGUAAGUCCUGUUAAACCUCUUUUUCUUCCUAGUCUUGGGUAUGCCUUUAUCAGUAGCAUGAAAAUGGUCUAGUAUAUUCAGUUAGAAAGGAGUUAAGAUGAUGAAAUUAUAUUUCAUGCUAGGGCCUUUAAUGAGGCAAAGAAGUAGGAAUCUAGGUAUCUUGCAGUCUAAGUUGUCAUAGAGUUCAAGUCCACUGGGGUUUUACCUGAGGACUCUGCUAAACAGAGUUUACUCUUGUUAUCUUGCAAUUAUGAGCACCAAAAAGGACGUGUAUGUGUUACUGUUAGGACAUAAAGCAUGUAAAAUGGGCUCCUCAGUAUCCUUGCUCAGUUCACUGUACUCAGAAUGGCAAGUACUGGCAACCCUUUGUGUCUGUGCUGAGAGUGCAAGUUGAUAUUCAGGGGCCUCUACUCCUAGGAAUUGGCCACGAUCUUUUCUCUAGGCUGCCUGCUGAUUCCCUUAGUAUGUUCUAAUUUGAGUAAUAAUGAGAUUUCUCAGGAUCGUUUUGAUUUGACUUCUUUCCUCAGUUUUGCUUCUUGGGGAUGGAUAGGGUAGGGUUAGUUCUCAGGCUACAUGAGAAUCUUCUUUGGUUGCUACAUUUUGAAGUUGUGCAAGAGCUGGAUGUACGUUUUCCCUUAUUUUGGUUGUUGCUGAUAAAUUUUUUGACUGCCUUUUCUGGUUGUGGAUUUUUUGCUUUGGUUUUAUGUUUUUUCCCUGUUUAAUUACUCAUUCAUCAAAAGUCUUUAUAAACAUAUUAAUUAGAUGUUUCCCUAGUAAAGUUGAUACAUAAUGAAAGUUUGUAUAUGCGUAUAUUAAAAACAUAAUGGCUGUACAGUACCAUGAAAUUUCAGUGACCAUUUUUGUGCCUGUGUUUACAUUGUUGUUAGUGCAAAGUGGCCACCCAAAAUAUUUAACUUUGUUAAUAAACAUAUCUAGCUGCUCUUUGCAACACAGACACCUGCCAUAGUACUCAUUAAAUUUUCUACUAGUUAUAAAGACUUAGUUAGCUAUGAUAGUUCACAAUUAAAAGACACUCUCAUAUAAUUAGAUGUAGUUUCUUAACAAAUUGAGAGUUUAACAAGUUGAAUUAAAAAUUCAUGAAGAAAAGAGUGCAGUGUAGUGGUAUAUACUUUUACAGUUACAGGGUAAUGAGAAUGGACUUAAUACUUAAAUAAUACAUGACAGAAAUUAUGGUGUGCCUACUGAAGUUUGAUUAUCUUGAAAGUUCAACAGAGCCUUGACAUUUUUACUAGUUUCUACUUAUGUGAAUAAGCAUUUAUUUUGAUAUUAUUUUAAGCAAAAUGCAAAAGCAGAUUAAAUACGAAACUGGCCUGAGCUACAUUUUUCCAAUGCUUAAAAAAAAUGCCCUGCCUUAAUUAGGUUGAAGGCUAGGCUGAUGUAAGAGAAGCCUGGAGAACAUAGGUUUUUUUUGGUUUUUCUUUUUUUUUGGUCACAAAACAACCCAAAAUAGUUAGACAGUUCUGCUUUGUGCUGUCAUUUAAGGACCCAGGUUCCUUUCAUCUUAUUGCUUUGAUGUCCCCUCACCCCUUGCUACUCCAAGUGUGGUCCACAGGCCAGCAGCAUUGAUAUCACCUGGUAGCUUGUUAGAAGUGUAGAAUCUCAAACCUCACCAGCAUCUUAAUUUUAGUAAGAUUCUUAUUAAAGAAUCUUAUUGCACAUUAAAGUGAUUCUUUUGCACAUUAAGGUUUGAGGAGCAGCACUUUAGGGUAUUGUCAUUGUCUUCAUGGUCAUAGCAGAGUAGCUGACAAAUUUGGGUUUCCCUAGCUGGAAUGGGAAGAACAGCAGAGAGCCAUAGAGUCAGUUCCCUGAGGAAGAGAGACAUCGUAUCCUUGGUUUCUAAGAACUUUAAUCUGACAUCUACCUGAAAGGGAUUCUGAGAACUGUGGCCUAGCUCAGUGACUCUCAAACAAACAACUAGUUAAAUCUUAUAAACUGUAAAACCUUGUGGUAGUGUGAGAUUGCUCCAAAAGUUUCUGUACAUAUCCAAUCAUGUGACAGUAACAGAGUUUGUGGAUUGGCAUUAAUCCAUGAACCACACUUGAAGUAGGUCAUAUUUGACAUAUUUGAAUUUUUCAUUCAGUGAUAUUGUUCAGCUUACGGUAAAUUUGAGUGAAUUGGUGUGAGUAAAUGAGGCUCUAUUUUUUUGGCCUUUGAUACUUUUUGAUUUAGUUUACUUAAUAUUCUUCUACUUUUUAAAAAAUAGUGAUAUCACUUAUUUUUAGUGAUAAUCUUACGUUUGUAAGGACUUUUCAGCUUGAAAAGCCCUUUUCCCUACAUUAUAUGGCAUUCUAUAAUAGUAGGUAGUAUGGACUGUAUUUGCUUAUAAAAAGGGAUUACAAGCCUUGUUGGUUUAAUCAUGCUGAUAACUAGUAUGACACAUCAAGAAAUGGAUGCUUUUUUAAUGAAAUGAUGCCUUCUUUUUAUGUAUUUUGUAACUUUCUUAUACUUUUAGUUAUUAAUUAGUAUUUGUUUUGAAUUGGUGUUAUGAAACUUAUCUGGGCCAUUAUAUUGGCCAACUGCUUGAUUUUUUUUGUUAUUAUUCUUGCCUUGACAUGUUUUCAUGGAAAAUAAAAUUGAAUUGGACUGUUAGUGGUCUUUUAAAAUGGUUUACCUUAUCGCAGUAGCUUUCAUUUCAUGUGUAAAUUAAAUUGCUUAUCAUUAUUCUUAAACAUUUGCUUAAAGUAAUGCUUUAAGCAAAAGUAUAUGUAAAAUAUGAUUAUAGAUCUCUACAUAUCUAAGAUGCGUACUUUAAAAGUUGAAAUACAGGCUCAUGUUUGACUGAAUGUUUUUGUUAUUUUCAACUUGCUUUUUGCUGUUACGGCCUGCCUGGUAUUCCCUGCAGUAUCCCUGUACUCCCAAUUUUUUUUUUUUUUGCCUAAGUACCCAAUAUAUAUGAACUAAUAGGUCAACAGGAAGUUAGCAUGUGAAAAUGCUGCCAAGGAAUGGGCCCAAAAGCUUGAAUCACUUUGUGUUUGAAACUGAGAUGUGUAAAUUAAAUGAUUUUGAAUAAACAUUUAUAUUAGAAUUAGUUAAUUAUAAUUAAUUAGAAUUUCAUCACAAAACUGAAUUAUUGUGAGAGAUUACUGAGGAAAAAAAUAGUUACAAAAACACUGCCAUGUACCUUUUAUAUUCAGUUAGAUAUAUAUCUGCUUGAGAAGCUGUAUGGCUGGUGUUUACGAGCAUGGGCUCUUGAAGACCAAUUCUCCUGAGCUGAGAUCAGUCCUGGUUCUGCCACAGAUUAGCUAUAACCUUGGGCACAUUUCUUAACUGCUCAUGUCUCAGUUUGCUUAUCUAUAAAAUGGUGUCAAUAUUAUACCUACUUCAUAGUAUUGUUAGGAGGAUUAAUAAGUUAAUACACACAAAGUGCUUAGAAUACUGCUUGGCAUAUGCUGAAUGCCCAGUAAAUACUUAAUGUUCUUGCUGUUGUAUGUCAAGACUGGACUCACUUAAAUUAGUGUUGUCAGUUAAAUACAUUCAUGUUACUUGCACACAUGAAUUUCUGAUCUUGUGUCACCUUUGGAAAAAGUUGAUGCCCUUUACUCUAUUUUAGAUUACCUUAUAUAGCCUGUGAGAGUGUUACUUCAAUAAAGAUAAAAUCUUUAUAUCUUAUGGAUUUUUAAUCUCAAAUAUAUAUAUCAUACCAUUAGCAUUUUAUAAUCUUAUAAAUAUUAGUGUCUCAAAUUAAAGAUAAAAGGUACAGGUAGAAUAUUUCACAUAAUAUUACAUUAUUUCACUUGUACAGGAAGAAUAGAAAUUUGAGAGAGGAAACUGUCAAUAUUCAGUCUCUUAAUAUGGACAUGAACUUAAGUCUCAGCUGAAGGGAGGUAUUUUCAUAUUCUUGUUGAAAUGUUGCAUUGUUAUUAAGUAUUUGCCUUAUAUUUUUAUAAAUAAGGAUUUCACUUAAAGAAUAAUGUGUUGCCCUCCUCAAAAAUUAAAUGUGUGGAACCAGUUGUGCAAUAUGUAAAUUUGUGAGACAAUGUACGUUUUUUUUUAAGUCCAGAUACAUUUUUUUUGAGAGAAGGACAUGUCUAUUACAUCUAGUUUUUGAAGAAAGAAAGAUUAUAUAGCUUUAUCCUAAGGAGUUGGCAGACUAUGACCAGUGGGCCAAAUCUGGCCUGCUACCAGUUUUUGUAAAUAACAUUUUAGUAGAACACAGCCAGAACCACUCAUACACCUACUGUCUGUAGCUGCUUUUGUGCUACAGGAGCAAAGAGUAGUUGUGACAGAAAUCAAAUAUUGUAGGAAAGCCUGCAAUAUUUACUAUCUGGUUCUUUACAGGAAAAGUUAGCCAAUCUCUGCCCUAAGUAAUUAGUAAAAUAGAUAUAUUAAUUCUUUAUUACUUAGAAAAAACUGAAGUUGGAACAAGUAGUAUAUGCUAUUGGUACCAGAAUUUGUCAAAAAUAACUUGCCAAGAAAACCACAAUCCUUGUUCUUAUCCUUAUUUGUAGUGACUAGUAUGAAUAGGGCUGCCUCAUAAAUUAGUAAAUCCUAACUAUUUGAUAGGAAUGUGUCAGUACUUGCAGUGGGGGCUUUUUGUCAAAUACAGAGUUAUCAGGUGUUUUGAAAUGGUCUACUAAUUUUAAUAGAACUUUCCAUUAUAUCCUAGGGCAGAUAGAAAUCCUUCAUUGGUUUCAAUUGAGCAUUCCUAUCACACUUGGACAACUUUUGGAUUCUGUAGAAUACCUAGACAACAGACAGUGGUUUUUUUUUUCUGUUUUUGUUUUUAAAAAAUAAAAUCAGUACUGCUUAAACAGAGGGAAAAGGGUGAAUAUGAGGUUGAAAAACCUGUUAAAACACAUCAGUCUUGAGUAAAAUAUAGGAGGAGUUUGUUCUUAGAUAUCAAAAUAUAUUUGGUAGCCAAUCAUAUUUAAAUUAAACUGAUUGGUCAUCAGCAUACUGAUUAUUUUAUAUAAGAAAUUGAACUUAUGAAAAAAAAAUUCAUGUGUUGAUUUGACCAAGAUUGAUGUUUUAUAACAGUGUUUAGGGAACUAGGCAUGAAGGGCCUAAUGAGAUCCUGUUUUACAAUAUUCAUUGCCAUUCUCAUUCAUAUUUUUCCUUUUUAGAUUUGUGUUCUGAAACUUUGAGAAUUACCAAUUCCACUCUGUGGACAUUCAUAUCAACCGGGAUCCAGUGCACAAUUUUCAUUUUUGAUGUUAUUCUGAUUAUAUUAUUAUUUUAUUAUCAGAUUAUAUUAUUCUGAUUACAUUACUAUUUCAUCAGAAUCUUUACGCUUCAGCCAACCACUUGGGUGUAUCAGGACUAUAAUUAACAUAUUGGUAAUAAGCAAACAUACUCAUUUAACAAAUGUAAGCAAUAAUAGGCAAAUGCCAUUAUUGGGAAAACUAGGCCCUCAAUGUUAGCUAACUAAACAGACCAAUGCAAUCUUUAUAACUCAUUCACACACUUAAAGAAUAUGAGAAUUUUGAAGAGUACAUUAAUUUUUCUGUAAAACAUGAUUAAUAUCAAAUUGUAAGAUGUAUGCAAAUAAAAUUGCUUUCUUUUCUCAAAUGGGCAAGCUUUGUACAGAUGCCUUGAUGGAUCUUCCGGGAACUACCAUGUCCAGAGAUUUAUUGAGUUUUAAAUAAGAGCCAUGAAAAGAUCAGAUUUGCCAAGUUUACAAAGAUAGUUCUGGCCUUUAUUUCAAGGAUAGGUGAAGAGAUCAAGGCUCAAGCAAAGACAAUUUACGGAAAAACAUUCUUUAGAGACAAACUUCAUCAAUAUAUCUUUUUCUUAAGGAAAAGUGAAGAAAGGGAGAACUCUGGUUGGCCGUCAGUGUCCUUGACUUGUCUCCUUCCCCUAUUUAAAAAUAGAAUCAGUUAAUAAUGUUUAUUAGUGUUAAUGUUGGACAUUUUAAAAUACCCUUUGCUUAAGAAUUAAUAACUUUGUUGGAUGGCUCAAAAAUUGUGUUUUGGAAGUUGAUAAGGUAUUGAUUUUAGAUUUAACAUGGUACAAUAUCAAAUCAUGGCAAAAAUGAUCCACUUUAUGAUUUCACUGACUCUUUUCAAUAAUUAAGGUUUCUCUAAGUGUAAAGUGUAAAGAUUUUUAGAGGAAGAUGUGGAAGUACUCAUAAUAUAGUUCUUAGUCUAAAUUUCUAAUGAGAUUUUUUUUUUAACUAAGGAAGUUUUAAGAACAGAUUUACAAAACAGUGAUUAUUGAAAGAUGGUGAUACUUGCUCUUACCUUUCCCAUGAUCAGUUGAGCUGAUAUGGUCAACUACUAAUUCCAUUCUUAGUGCUAUUUCCAAAGCAGUAUGUGAAUGAAGCUGUAUUUAAAACAUUCAUUUACCAAGUAGAUAUUUAUUAAGCAAGACUUUUUUCUCCAAAAUCUGAGUUUCCUUUUUUAAGAAAAUAUUUUACGAAUGCCUUUUCUUGUUGUUGUAAUGUUUAGCACAUGUAUGACUGUGUUCAUGUGCACAUUUGUUUGCAUUAGUCUUACUUAUAGCUACUGUUUCUUUGGGCUGUCUGCUACAGUCUGGCUUGUGCUUCUUCCACACUGCUGAAAUGCUUUUGCUAAAGUACCAGUGACCUUCCAGUUGUGAGAUAUCUUUCAAAUUUUUCCUUACUGGCUCUGUUACUUUGGACGGUUUAUGUCUAUCUUGGAAUUCACUGUUAAGACAUAGUGUCUUAAAAUUCACUAUUCCUUGUCUCCCCUAACACUGUUCUCCUCAUCUUGUUCUUGUUCUCUUCAUUCCUUUCUCAUCAUUCGUUGUCUUUUUAUGAUAUUCUUAUCAUACCUUUCCCUGGCUUUUCUUAGUUUCCUUAUUGGUACUAACAAAGUUCUAUCUUUGGUCCACUUUCUUGUUCUUCUGACUUUAACUGAUCAGUCUCUCUCUCUCUUUUUUUUUUUUUUUGAGUCCAGGUCUUAUUCUGCUGCCCAGGCUGGAGUACAGUGGCAUAAUCAUAGCUCACUGCAGCCUCAAUCUCCUUGGGUCAAGUGAUAAACCCACCUCAGCCUCCCAAGUAGCUAGGACUACAGGCACACACCACCCCACAUGGCCAAUUUUUUAUUUUAGUAGAGAUGGGCUCUUGCUAUGUUGUCCAGGCUGGUCUGAAACUCCUGGCCUCAAAGGGCUUCUCCUGCCUCAGCCUCCCAAAGUGCUCGGAUUACAGGUGUGAGCCAUUGUACUUGACCCAGUCUCAUUUGCUUUCAUGAUUUAAACUAAUUUCAUUUUUUUUUUUUUUUUUGAGAUGGAGUCUCACUCUGUUGCCCAGGCUGGAGGCUAUCCCAGCUCACUGCAACCUUUGCCUCCUGGAUUCAAGUGAUUCUCUUGCCUCAGCCUCCUGAGUAGCUGGGAUUACAGGCUCCUGCCACCAUGCCCAGCUAAUUUUUGUAUGUUUAGUAGAGAUGGAGUUUCACCAUGUUGGCCAGGCUAAUCUUGAACUCCUGACUUCAGGUGAUCCACCUGCCUCGGCCUCCCAAAGUGUUGGGAUUACAGGUGUGAGCCGCCACACUGGCCGAUUUAAACUAAUUUCUAUAUACUGAUGAUUCCUAAAUCUUUCUGGGCCUGAACUUCAAAAUACAGCCUUAUAUAUGAAAUACUCUGCACAAUUCGAACUAGGUAUCCCAGGGGCACCUCGAACUCCUCAUGCCUUUCACUGUACUUCUCUUCCCCUCCAUCUCCCAAGUUCUUCUUCUCUUUACACUCUUGUUUUAGAGGUGGUACACUCAUCUCACCAUUCAUGAGUCAUUUUUUUCUUUUUCCUAUUCACUCAUAUCUAAAUUAAGAAUCAGACCUGCCAAUUUUACCUUCUAAAUAUUUUUCUACUUCAGGCCUUUAUUCUUGAGAGUAGCCUCCUGAUUGGUCUUCUUGCUUACUGUCUCAAAUCUGUCUUUUCUAUAGGUGUUAGAAUGAGUUAUCUAUAAAGGUUGUCUAAUCUUUAGAUCUUUUGUCACCUACAGGAUGAAGUCUGUCUUACAAAGGUAUGCAUAGCCUCUUGUUUCUUUGUGGCAUCCAUUUUUGCUCCUACCUCUCCAGCAGUUUAUGCUCUAACAAGACCAACUUGCUUGUGGGUCUCUUAUGUACAUGGUAUUUUAUGUCCUGCCACUGUACCAUUUCUGAUCUUGUCCUUUCUGCUUGGAUUUUUUUCUCCAUUUAAGUUAGUUAAUUAUUGUCCAUCAUUUUAAAACAUAACUGUCAUCUGUUAUAAGAAGUCUUCCCUGAUAGAAAGUAGGUACCCUUCUUCUGAGGUCCUUUAACAUUCUGUCUCUAGCUCAUUGUGCUAUAAUUGUUUAUAUGUUUGUCUCCUCAAGUAAACCAAGCUUCACUGGGACUAAACUUAUUUGAGGUCAGUACCAUGGUUUUUUCAUCUUUGAAUUCUUGGGACUAGUACAGUGUCUGCCACAGAGUAGAUAGAGACUCAACAAAUGUUUAUUGAAUAAAUAAACUGAAUGGACUUGUCUUUUUAAAUUGCAGCACAAUUAAUGUACAUUAAAAUGCACAGCUCUUAAGUGUUUAGCAUGAUAGGUUUUGAUAGUUGUGUACGUUUAAGUAACCCCCAUUCUAAAUGUUAUAUAGAAUGUUUUCAUCACCCAAGAAAGUUUUCUCCUGCUCUGUUCCUUCUGUGCCCACAGAUAGUCUUUUUCUGACAUCUGGCAUCAUGAAUUCACUAUCUUGUAAUUGGAUAUUAUAAAAAUGGAAACCUUAUUUCUUCUGACAUCUUAGAAGUAUAAUGCUUUUGAGAUUCAUUCAUAUUCUUGUCUGUAUUGGUAGUUCAUUUUUUAUUGUUGAGUAGUAGUUCCUGUUUGAGUAUACCAUAAUUUGUUUGGUCAUUCUCCUUUUGAUAGACAAUAACCAGUUUUUGGUUAUUAUGAAUAAGGCUUGGAGCAUUCAUUUAUAAGUAUUUUUUGUGGACAUAUGUUUUCAUUUCUCUUAGAGGAUAUCUAGGAGUGAAAUUGCUGGGCCAUAGGGCACAUUUUUGUUUAACUUUAUAGGAAACAGCCAAACGUUUAUUUCCAAAGUGGGUGUGACAUUUUAUACUCCAACCAACAGUGUAUGAGAGAUCUGGUUUCUCCACUUCCUCACCAAUAUUCUAUUUUCAGUCCUUUUGAUUUUAGCCGUUCAUCUGGUGUGAAAUGGUAUCUCAUUGUGGUUUUAAUGUGUAUUUUCUUGAUGGCUAAAGAUGUUGAGUACUUUUUAAUGUGACUAUUAGCUCUUCAUAAAGUAUCUAUUUGAGUCUUUUGUCCGUUAAGAAUUUGGAUUGUUGUACCUAUCACUGAUAGCCUAAAGAAAAUAUGGAACAUAUACACCAUGGAAUACUAUGCAGCCAUAAAAAAGAAUGAGUUCAUGUCCUUUGCAGGGACAUGGAUGCAGCUGGAAACCAUCAUUCUCAGCAAACUAACAUAGGAACAGAAAAACCAAACACCAUGUGUUCUCACUCAUAGGUGGGAGUUGAACAGUGAGAACACAUGGACACAGAGAGGGGAACAUCACACACUGAGGCCUGUUGUGGGGGCGGGGGGCAAAGGGAGGGAGAACAUUAGGACAAAUACCUAAUGCAUGUGGGGCUUAAAACCUAGAUGAUGGGUUGAUAGAUGCAGCAAACCACCAUGGCACAUGUAUACCUAUGUAACAAACCUGCACAUUCUGCACAUGUAUCCCAGAACUUAAAGUAAAAUAAAAAAAAAAGAAUAGAUGGAUGAAAGCAGAAAGGAAGAAAAGGAAUAAUCUAAAGUAAAUAUGGUAAAAUGCUAAUAUUUUAAAAAUCUAGGUGGUGUGAGCAGGAAUUUUUAAAAAUUAUUUUUAAUGUUUUUCCUAUAAGUAAAAAUAUUUCAUAUUAGAAGACAAAAAGAGAUGAAAAGGUAUUUUCAUCUCUCUUAUAAUUAUUGUGGUUAUGUGUUUUAUAUGUAAUACAUCAUGUAAUGAUAGAUAUACUAGAUUAUUAAUAUUACAAAUAUAGACUUAGAAGAUAGAUAUCAUUUACAUCAAGUUAAUCAGUGUAUAAGAAGUAUGAUUUUUUCUACUUGUAAUUAUUUCCAUAAAGGUUAAUGUUUUUUACCUAACAACAACAACAACAAAAAGAAAUUGGAUUGUUGGACUUCUUAAUGUUGAUUUGUAGGAGUUGAUUAUAUGUUCUAGAUAUGAGUCUUAAAAUACAUAUGCUAUGAAUGUUUUUUACAAUCUGUGGCCUUUUUACUUUAUUAAUGAUAUUUUUUGAUGACUAAAUAUUUUUAAUUUUGGUCAAGAUCAAUUUUAUCAGUUUUUUUUUUCUUUUAUAAUGAGGGCUUUUUAUGUCCUGUUCAAGAAUUGUUGCCUACUUCAAGUUUGUGAAGGUACUUUCUUAUGCUUGCUUCCAGAAGCUGUAUGAUAUGGGUUUUAUAUUUAAGUAUAUGAUCAAAUUAUGUUGGUUUGUGGAGUGGGAAAGAAGCAUGGUAUUAUUUUUAUUUUUAUACAGAUAUUCAGGUAUUUCAGUGACAUUUGUAAAAAAAAAUUUUCUUUAUUGGAUUGACUUGGCAUUUUGAUUGAAAAUCUGUUGACCAGGCUGGGCGUGGUGGCUGAUGCCUGUAAUCCCAGUGCUUUGGGAGGCCGAGGCGGGUGGAUCAUGAGGUCAGGAGAUCAAGACCAUCCUGGCUAACAUGGUGAAACCCCGUCUCUACUAAAAAUACAAAAAAAAUUAGCCGGGCGUGAUGGCGGGCGCCUGUAGUCCCAGCUACUCGGGAGGCUGAGGCAGGAAAAUGGCAUGAACCCAGGAGGCGGAGCUUGCAGUGAGCCGAGAUCACGUCACUGUGCUCCAACCUAGGUGACAGACUGAGACUCCGUCUCAAAAAAAAAGAAAAUCUGUUGACCGUAUUUUGUGGGUCUAUAUUGUUUUAUUAUUCUAUUUGACUGUCCUCAUGCCAAUAUCACACUGUCUGGAUUAAUGAAGCUUUAUGAUAAGUACUGAUAACAAUUAGUGUGAGCCCUCAUCUUUUCUUUCAGGUUAAUUUGGGAAUUCUUGAGCAUUUGCGUUUCCAUAUUGUAUUAGUUCAUUUUCAUACUGCUGUGAAGAAAUACCCGAGACUGGGUAAUUAAUAAAAAAAAAGAGGUUUAAUGGACUCACAGUUCCAUAUGGCUCAGGAGGCCCCACAAUCUUGGCAGAAGACGAAGGAGGAGCAAAGGCACAUCCUACAUGGUGGCAGGCAGCAGAGCAUGUGCACAGGAACUGCCCUUUAUAAAACAAUCGGAUCUCAUGAGGCUUACUUACUAUCACGAGAAUAGCAUAGGAAAAACUUGCCUUCUUGAUUCAAUUACUUCCCACUGGGUCCCUCCUGUGACACAUGGGGAUUAUGGGAGCUACAAUUCGAGAUGAGAUUUGGGUGGGGACACAGCCAAACCAUAUCACAUACGAAUUUUAACAUCAGUUUGUCUAUUUGCUGAAGAAAAUCCUACUAGGACUUAUGAUAACUAGAAAAUGGUGGCAGUGUAGUAAAUAACUUCCCAAAAUCUUUCCCCCAAACUAUACGGAUGACUUCACACCUAAGCAAAAUCUGUGUAAAACAAUGCUCUCAACCUUAUGUGAGCACAGAGAAUGUGGAAACUAUCAAAGACCUGUGAGUAAAAAGAAAAAGUUAAAAGCCAGCCCCAUGGUUCCACACACUCCUGUGCCAAUCUUGUCCCACUUGUGGGGCUUUGGUGAUCCAAGGCAGACCUCGAAAAAAACUACAGAAAAGCAGAGGAGAGAUGCAAAUGAAAUGACUGGAGGGUGGUAGGAAUGACCACCAGAAAGAUCAAAUCCACCCUAAAUGUGAAAAAUAAAGAAAUUUGGCUUAUUAGGAAGAUAUUUCAAAGUAAGGACAGGUGCCAAGUAAAGGGCCAGAAAGAAACAGAUGAAAAACAGUGGGUCAGGCAUGUAACUUAAAAUAGACACAUGCCAUAUAAAGGAAUUGGUGUGUGAAUUAAAGGGAUAGAUUCUAUUUAAAUGGGUAAGUCUGAUUUCAAAGAAUAGGUACGAUUUAAAGGGUUCAAUUUUUGAAAUGCAUAGCUUCUGGGGGAGAAAGAAACAAAAAGGAGGGAAGGCGUUUCCUUUGGCAAUUGGAUAAUGAAGAGGAAAAGAAGGAAAAGGGAAAAAUUAAGGCCCUGUGAGACAAAAUAGAACUACACAGGUGGAGGAUUCAUAAUAUGCCCCCUAAUGAAACCAACCACUUCAUUAAAGUAUAUAGCAUGGAUUGACUGGUAGGAAAGGGUGACAUUGGACUAGAAAUAUUGUAAAACAGCCCAAUGUCACAAAAAUGAACAAAAUAUUUCUAAAUCAGGAAACAAAUUUGCACGCAAACCUAGGAAAAUUCUUUUUCCCCAAAACAACCGUGAACUAUAACUCUAAGUUCAUACUCCAACAGAAUUAAAUUUACUCCAACGAGCAUUUGGAAGUAUGAAAAAUCACUUGAGUCAGAAAUUAAAAAACUAAAGACAGAAGUGGACAAUAAACAGGGACAAAUGGGGGAAAAUGUUGAUGGAGCUUUGGAAAGAAAUGGAAGAAAAUAUCAGAAUUAUUUUAGAAAUAAAGAAUAUAUUACAAGAUACCCAAGGGAAAAUGGACUAGAAUGAAAAAUUGAUAAGGAGCAUUGAAGAAAGAAAAACAACUAUGAGAAUUUAAAUAAGAAAUGUCAGAGAGAAAGUAGUCGAAUAUUAUUCCUUUGGAAUAAUAUUCAAGUCAAGGAAGGAAUAAUAUUUGUUUUAUUUGAGUCCCUAAGGGGAAAAAACCAAAACAAUUGAAAAGAGCUGAUAUCUAAAACUAUAAUUCAAGAAAACUUUCCAGAUGGAAAAAGAUGUAAAUCCACACAUUGAAAGUAUGUCAAGUGCAAUGAAAGAUUAAUCCACAGCAAUUAACUCCAAGACAUAUCCCAGUUAAAAAUUAUCAGAUUAUUAAGAUAAUAAAAUCCUUAGGACCGACAUGAAACAAGUCAAAUAAAAGCAAAAGAAUUAUAGUAGCAUCAAGCUUUUCAAAACCAAUAUAUAAAGCAAGGCAGAAAUAGAGCAGCAUUCAAAGAAAAGUCAGUGGAAGUAUGAAUUUGGGAUUUUAUAUCUAGCCAAGCUGCUUUUUAAAUAUUAAGGCCAUAUAAAAAUAGUUUUCAUCAUACCAGAACUUUUAUGCAUCAAGAGAUAGAGCAACUGGCUUUCUGAAACAGAAACUUCAGGAGUUUGCAGGGACACAUACAUAGAAACAUACCAGUAACAGGAUACUUCGUUAUACUGCUUUCAUUACUAGUAAUGAUAGAUUUAAGUGGACAAAAUAUAAGGAGGUAGAAGAUGUAAACAAUAUAGCCAAUAAGGUUGAUCUUCUGGGUAUACUGUAUAUUGAAUGCUAUACCUCGAUAAGAGAAAAUACUCAUUUUCUUAAGUGCCUAUGGCACAUUCACAAAAACUGAUUAUAUAUUAUGUCAUAAGGAAAACAUUAAUAACUUCCAUAAAGUAGAACUAUUAUAAACACUCUGAUUACAGUGGACUAAAACUAGGAUUUACUAACAAAACCAAAUACAAGCCCUUUCACCUAGAAAUUAAAAAGUUUGACUAAACAACUUUUUAAAAAGUAUUUUAAAAAAUUGUAAAAGGAGAAAUACAAUUAAGUGUAUUUAAUUGUAAAAAAAUGUAAUGACAGUGACACUUUAUAUCAUAAUUUAUGUGGUAUAUUUAAAGCAGUGAUUAGAGGAAAAUUUAUUUUACUGCUUUUAUUAAUAAAAUGAAUAAAUGAACUAAAUUUUCAGCGAAACUAAAAAAGAUCAAGGUAAGUCAAAAGAAAGGAAGAAAAAUAAUAACUAUAAAAGCAGAAAUUGAUGAGCAAAAGAAUAGAAAAACAGUAAAUCUAGCAAAUAAGCCAAAAUCCUGAUGUUUUCUCUCCCUGGCCAUGCAGUGGUUUUUUUUGUUUGUUUGUUUUUGUUUUUUGAGAUGGAGUCUUACUCUGUCGCCCAGGCUGGAGUGCAGUGGCGCCAUCUUGGCUCACUGCAAGCUCCGCCUCCCGGGUUCACGCCAUUCUCCUGUCUUAGCCUCCCGAGUAGCUGGGACUACAGGCGCCCGCCACCAUGCCCGGCUAAUUUUUUGUAUUUUUGGUGGAGACGGGGUUUCACUGUGUUAGCCAGGAUGGUCUGGAUCUCCUGACCUCGUGAUCCACCCACCUCGGCCUCCCAAAGCGCUGGAAUUACAGGCGUGAGCCACCGCCCCCAGACAGUGGUUUUUAAAAAACAACUUUAUUGAGUUAUAAAUCACAGAAAAAAAUUCACCUCUUUAAAGUGUACAGUUCUGGCUGGGCGCAGUGGCUCACGCGUGUAAUCCCAGCACUUUGGGAGGCUGAGGUUGGCGGAUCACUUGAGGGAGGAGUUCGAGACCAGCCUGGCCAACAUGGCAAAACCCCUUCUCUACUAAAAAUACAAAAAUUAUCUGGGCAUAGUGGGAUGCUCCUGUAGUCCCAGCUACUCCGAAGGCUGAGGCAGGAGAAUUGCUUGAACCCAGGAGGCAGAGGUUGCAGUGAGCAGAGAUUGUGCCACUGUACCCCAGCCUGCGCAACAGAAGGCAACUCUGUCUGAAAAAAUAAAUAAAAAUAAAGCAUAUCAUUCAGUAGCUUUUCGUAUAUUCACAGAGAUUUGUAAUCAUCACUACUAUCUAAUUCAAGAACAUUUAACCCGAUAUGCAUUGGCAUCAUUCCCCUUUCCUCCUAGACCCUGGCAACUUCUCAUCUGCUUUCUGUCUCUAUGGAUUUUUUUAUAUGACGUUUCAUAUAAGUGGAAUCAUACAGAUUGUGGCUUUUAAUGUUUGGCCUCUUUCAUUUAGCAUAACAUUUUUAUGGUUCAUUCAUGUUGCUGCAUGUAUCAUUCCUUCACUUAUUUUUAUGACAAUAAUAUUACAAUGUGUGGAAAUAACACAUUUUGUUUAUAUUCAUUUAUCGGAUGAACAGUCUUGGUGUUUUUGAAAAAGUUAACAAAAUAGACAAACCAUUAGCUAACUUAUUCAAGGAAAAAAUGCAUAACUAUGUAAAAUAAGAAAUAACAAAGAGAAGUCAUCUUUGAAACAGAAUACAUUAAAAAUAAUUUGAUUAAAAAAUGGGCAAACGAUCUGAAUAAACUUUUCCCCAAAGAAGACAUAAAAAUGUCUAAGAGGUGUAUGAAAAGGUGCUCAAGAUCACGAAUGAUCAGGGACAUGCAAAUUGAAACCACUAUGAUGUAUCACCUCACACCUAUAAGGAUGGCUAUUAUCAAAAAAGAUACAAGAUAACAAAUGUUGGCAGGGGUGUGGAGAAACACCCUAGUACACCGUUGAUGGGAAUGUAGAUGGGUACAGCCCUUGUGGAAAACAGUAUGGAAACUCCUAAAGAAAUUAAAAAUAGAACUACAGUAUGACCUAGCAAUCCCUAUUCUGAGUAUAUAUCCAAAGAAGAUGAAAUCACUACCUCAUAAAGAUAUUUGCACUUCCAAGUUUAUUGCAGCAGUAGUCACAGUAGCCAAGCUAUGGAAACAAUCUAAUGUCCAUCGAUGGAAAAAUGAAUAAAGAAAAUGUGGUAUAUACAGUUGAUCUUGAACAGUACGGAUUUGAACUGUGUGAGUUCACUUAUACGUGGAUUUUCUUUGAUUUCUACCAUGCCACCACUGAGACAGCAAGACCAACCCCUCCUCUUCUUCCUCCUCCUCAGCCUACUCAACAUGAAGACAAUGAGGAUGAAGACCUUAAUGAUGGUCUCUUUCCACAUAAUGAACAGUAUCUUUCAGAUGAAGGCAUUGAAGCUUGCACAAGCUCUCCAGACAAAGUCAAUGUAAAUGACAUCAUCCUGAUUGCUCUCAAUACAGAUCUGAGAACAAUUGGCAAGAAAUUCCUCCCCAGUGACAUCAAUAGUGGAAAGGUAGAAAAGCUCGAAGGUCCAUGUGUUUUGCAAAUUCAAAAAAUUCGCAAUGUUGCUGCACCAAAGGAUAAUGAAGAAUCUCAGGCUGCACCAAGGAUGCUGCGAUUACAGAUGACUGAUGGUCAUAUAAGUUGCACAGCAGUAGAAUUUAGUUAUAUGUCAAAAAUAAGCCUGAACACACCACCUGGAACUAAAGUUAAGCUCUCAGGCAUUGUUGACAUAAAAAAUGGAUUCCUGCUCUUGAAUGACUCUAACACCACAGUUCUUGGUGGUGAAGUGGAACACCUUAUUGAGAAAUGGGAGUUACAGAGAAGCUUAUCAAAACACAAUAGAAGCAAUAUUGGAACUGAAGGUGGACCACCGCCUUUUGUGCCUUUUGGACAGAAGUGUGUAUCUCAUGUCCAAGUGGAUAGCAGAGAACUUGAUCGAAGAAAAACAUUGCAAGUUACAAUGCCUGUCAAACCUACAAAUGAUAAUGAUGAAUUUGAAAAGCAAAGGACGGCUGCUAUUGCUGAAGUUGCAAAGAGCAAGGAAACCAAGACAUUUGGAGGAGGUGGUGGUGGUGCUAGAAGUAAUCUCAAUAUGAAUGCUGCUGGUAACCGAAAUAGGGAAGUUUUACAGAAAGAAAAGUCAACCAAAUCAGAGGGAAAACAUGAAGGUGUCUAUAGAGAACUGGUUGAUGAGAAAGCUCUGAAGCACAUAACGGAAAUGGGCUUCAGUAAGGAAGCAUCGAGGCAAGCUCUUAUGGAUAAUGGCAACAACUUAGAAGCAGCACUGAACGUACUUCUUACAAGCAAUAAACAGAAACCUGUUAUGGGUCCUCCUCUGAGAGGUAGAGGAAAAGGCAGGGGGCGAAUAAGAUCUGAAGAUGAAGAGGACCUGGGAAAUGCAAGGCCAUCAGCACCAAGCACAUUAUUUGAUUUCUUGGAAUCUAAAAUGGGAACUUUGAAUGUGGAAGAACCUAAAUCACAGCCACAGCAGCUUCAUCAGGGACAAUACAGAUCAUCAAAUACUGAGCAAAAUGGAGUAAAAGAUAAUAAUCAUCUGAGACAUCCUCCUCGAAAUGAUACCAGGCAGCCAAGAAAUGAAAAACCGCCUCGUUUUCAAAGAGACUCCCAAAAUUCAAAGUCAGUUUUAGAAGGCAGUGGAUUACCUAGAAAUAGAGGUUCUGAAAGACCAAGUACUUCUUCAGUAUCUGAAGUAUGGGCUGAAGACAGAAUCAAAUGUGAUAGACCGUAUUCUAGAUAUGACAGAACUAAAGAUACUUCAUAUCCUUUAGGUUCUCAGCAUAGUGAUGGUGCUUUUAAAAAAAGAGAUAACUCUAUGCAAAGCAGAUCAGGAAAAGGUCCCUCCUUUGCAGAGGCAAAAGAAAAUCCACUUCCUCAAGGAUCUGUAGAUUAUAAUAAUCAAAAACGUGGAAAAAGAGAAAGCCAAACAUCUAUUCCUGAUUAUUUUUAUGACAGGAAAUCACAAACAAUAAAUAAUGAAGCUUUCAGUGGUAUAAAAAUUGAAAAACAUUUUAAUGUAAAUACUGAUUAUCAGAAUCCAGUUCGAAGUAAUAGUUUCAUUGGUGUUCCAAAUGGAGAAGUAGAAAUGCCACUGAAAGGAAGACGAAUAGGACCUAUUAAGCCAGCAGGACCUGUCACAGCUGUACCCUGUGAUGAUAAAAUAUUUUACAAUAGUGGGCCCAAACGAAGAUCUGGGCCAAUUAAGCCAGAAAAAAUACUAGAAUCAUCUAUUCCUAUGGAGUAUGCAAAAAUGUGGAAACCUGGAGAUGAAUGUUUUGCACUUUAUUGGGAAGACAACAAGUUUUACCGGGCAGAAGUUGAAGCCCUCCAUUCUUCGGGUAUGACAGCAGUUGUUAAAUUCAUUGACUACGGAAACUAUGAAGAGGUGCUACUGAGCAAUAUCAAGCCCAUUCAAACAGAGGCAUGGGCUGGAAAACAUUUUCAGACACUGUGCUUUAUCCUGAAAGGAUUUGGUGAAAAGGGAUCUCUGAGCUCCAGGGGAGCUGGAAAUGCACAGGAGGAGUCAGAAGACCUGGGUUCGAGUCCUGGCUCUGCCACUUACUACCUAUGUGACUUUGGGAGGAAGAAGGCACCUACGAUCAAACUCUGGAGUUCCGUAGGGGAGGUGAUGGCCAGCCAAGACGAUCCACUCGGCCAACCCAACAGUUUUACCAACCACCCCGGGCUCGGAACUAAUAGGAAAAGUAGACUCUUUGUGAAGAAACGAGCCAGUGACUGAAACACCCUGGUGGAAACCUGUUGACAGACCUUCCACUUUCUCUUCAGAAUAAGUAGCUGUGGUGGAUAUUAUUAUUUGAAGAAAGAAAAAACAGAUUUUAGGGUGGAAAAAACAGUCAACUCACACAAAGAAUGGAAAAAAAUACUGAGUUAAAUUAAGCAAAUACCUUUUACAAGUGAAAGGAAGAAUUUUUCUUCUGCCGUCAAUAAAACCAUUGUGCUAUUAUUGUUUUA